AGUUGCCGCUGUCGUCCGCAGAGCCAGUUCCUAGCGCAGAGCCGCGCCCGCCAUGAGGGAGAUCGUGCACAUCCAGGCGGGCCAGUGCGGGAACCAGAUCGGCACCAAGUUUUGGGAAGUGAUCAGCGAUGAGCACGGCAUCGACCCGGCCGGAGGCUACGUGGGAGACUCGGCGCUGCAGCUGGAGAGAAUCAACGUCUACUACAAUGAGUCAUCGUCUCAGAAAUAUGUGCCCAGGGCCGCCCUGGUGGACUUAGAGCCAGGCACCAUGGACAGCGUGCGGUCUGGGCCUUUUGGGCAGCUUUUCCGGCCUGACAACUUCAUCUUUGGUAUGUUCAGGCAGACGCAUAUAUUUACACACAUACAAUGGAGCCAGCUGUAUACACUGUUUAGUACCCUAGUGUUCCUCCCUGGCUCCCCAGCAACGUAUUUUGAAGAUCUUUCCAUUUCACAAGUAUGGCUGCCUCAUUCCUGUUGAUGGCUGAUAGUAUCCUCUGCAGAGAUACCGCCGUGGAUUUAACCAGUCUUCAGUUGAUAGAAUUACCUCUUUAACAUGGAACAACCAGGUCAAAAUGUAUAUACAUCUUUAAAAUUGACCAGUAGCUACUUUGACUUGCCUAAAAACGUACCAGUGCAUCUGCUCAGCUGCACCGUUGGUGGGUGCCUGUUUCCCCGGCCCCUCCCUUUGGCUAACAGCACAUCAUGGAAUCACUUCACACCCUCCUUGUCGGUGACCAAGCAUGGUGAUGGCGCAGCCCUUUCCUGUUUAAACGGCACGGGACUCUCUUUGUUGCAGGCCAGACGGGUGCAGGGAACAACUGGGCGAAAGGGCACUACACGGAGGGCGCGGAGCUGGUGGACGCAGUGCUGGACGUGGUGCGGAAGGAGUGCGAGCACUGCGACUGCCUGCAGGGCUUCCAGCUCACGCACUCGCUGGGCGGCGGCACGGGCUCAGGCAUGGGCACGCUGCUCAUCAGCAAGAUCCGUGAGGAGUUCCCGGACCGCAUCAUGAACACCUUCAGCGUCAUGCCCUCGCCCAAGGUGUCGGACACGGUGGUGGAGCCCUACAAUGCCACACUGUCGGUGCACCAGCUGGUGGAGAAUACAGACGAGACCUACUGCAUCGACAACGAGGCGCUCUAUGACAUCUGCUUCCGCACUCUGAAGCUGACAACGCCCACCUACGGGGACCUCAACCACCUGGUGUCCGCCACCAUGAGUGGGGUCACCACCUCGCUGCGCUUCCCGGGCCAGCUCAAUGCUGACCUGCGCAAGCUGGCGGUGAACAUGGUGCCCUUCCCGCGCCUGCACUUCUUCAUGCCUGGCUUCGCGCCGCUCACCAGCCGCGGCAGCCAGCAGUACCGGGCCCUGACCGUGCCCGAGCUCACCCAGCAGAUGUUCGACGCCAGGAACAUGAUGGCCGCCUGCGAUCCGCGCCAUGGCCGCUACCUGACCGUGGCCACCGUGUUCCGCGGGCCCAUGUCCAUGAAGGAGGUGGACGAGCAGAUGCUGGCCAUCCAGAGUAAGAACAGCAGCUACUUCGUGGAGUGGAUUCCCAACAACGUGAAGGUGGCCGUGUGCGACAUCCCGCCCCGCGGCCUGAAGAUGGCCUCCACCUUCAUCGGCAACAGCACGGCCAUCCAGGAGCUGUUCAAGCGCAUCUCCGAGCAGUUCUCAGCCAUGUUCCGGCGCAAGGCCUUCCUGCACUGGUUCACGGGUGAGGGCAUGGAUGAAAUGGAGUUCACCGAGGCGGAGAGCAACAUGAACGACCUGGUAUCCGAGUACCAGCAGUACCAGGAUGCCACCGCCAAUGACGGGGAGGAAGCUUUUGAGGAUGAGGAAGAGGAGAUCGAUGGAUAGUCGGAAUAGAGCCGCCCCAACUCAGAUCCUACAACACGCAAGUUCCUUCUUGAACCCUGGUGCCUCCUACCCUAUGGCCCUGAAUGGUGCACUGGUUUAAUUGUGUUGGUGUCGGCCCCUCACAAAUGCAGCCAAGUCAUGUAAUUAGUCAUCUGGAACAAAGACUAAAAACAGCAGAGAAUUGCGGGUUCUACCCAGUCAGAAGAUCACACCAUGGAGACUUUCUACUAGAGGACUUGAAAGAGAACUGAGGGGCCACAAAAUAAACUUCACCUUCCAUUAAGUGUUCAAGCAUGUCUGCAAAUUAGGAGGGAGUUAGAAACAGUCUUUUUCAUCCUUUGUGAUGAAGCCUGAAAUUGUGCCGUGUUGCCUUAUAUGAAUAUGCAGUAUGGGACUUUGAAAUAAUGAUUCAUAAUAAAAUACUAAACGUGUGUCUUCA